GAUCAAAGCAGACACUGAAUAGUGUUCAGUGGUUGCCUCCCAUGGAUCAAUACAACCAUUCAAGCCUGGCUGAAUUUGUGUUCCUUGGCUUUGCCAGUGUGGGCUAUGUCAGGGGCUGGCUUUUUGUCCUGCUGCUAUUGGCAUACCUGUUCACCAUCUGUGGUAACAUGCUCAUCUUCUCAGUCAUCCGACUGGAUGCAGCUCUGCACACACCUAUGUACCACUUUGUCAGUGUUCUUUCCUUCUUGGAGUUGUGGUAUACAGCUACCACUAUCCCUAAGAUGUUGUCUAAUAUUCUCAGUGAGAAGAAAACCAUUUCUUUUGCAGGAUGCCUCCUUCAGACCUACUUCUUCCACUCCUUGGGAGCGUCUGAAUGCUACCUUCUUACAGCCAUGGCCUAUGAUAGAUACCUGGCCAUUUGUCGGCCCCUCCACUACCCUAUAAUUAUGACCACCACACUCUGUGCCAAGAUGGCUGCUGCUUGUUGGACUUGUGGCUUCCUGUGUCCCAUUUCUGAGGUCAUCCUUGCCUCCCAGCUCCCAUUUUGUGCUUACAAUGAAAUCCAACACAUUUUCUGUGACUUUCCACCUUUGCUGAGCUUGGCCUGCAAGGACACAUCUGCUAACAUUCUGGUGGACUUUGCCAUUAAUGCUUUCAUAAUUCUUAUCACUUUCUUCUUUAUCAUGAUUUCUUAUGCAAGGAUCAUUGGGGCUGUGCUGAAGAUAAAAACAGCAUCAGGAAGAAAGAAGGCCUUUUCUACCUGUGCCUCACAUCUUGCUGUGGUCCUCAUCUUCUUUGGGAGCAUCAUCUUCAUGUAUGUGCGGCUAAAGAAGAGCUAUUCCCUGACCCUUGACCGAACACUUGCUAUAGUUUACUCCGUACUAACACCAAUGGUCAAUCCAAUUAUCUACAGUCUUCGUAACAAGGAAAUCAUUAAAGCUAUCAAGAGGACCAUCUUCCAGAAGGGAGAUAAAGCUAGUCUUGCUCAUCUUUGACUUUCUUCCCAUGUCCUUUCUCACCUCAAUGUUCAAUUCAUAAAAGUUCCUUGAGUAAUCUUCCCAUCAUCACACAUGCUCUGAAUUUCAUUUCCUUUCACCUCUUCAAAGACUUCAUUUCUUUAUGAUUUUCUCAUUUUCUACAUCUUUAUUUCUAUUUUUUACUCGAUCACUUAUGUCAGCAUUUAAGAAUAUUUUAGUAUCUACAUACUUCUUUUUUUAAAAAAAAGCAUGUAUAUUUCCUAGGUCCACACAUUUCCAUCCAGCUAGAGAUCGAUUUCUCUGUUCCUUUUUCCAAUCAAACUUCUCAACACACCAUAUUUCCUCUUCUUUACUUCAUAUCCACUUCUCAACCCAUUCCAAUCUUAUUUUGGCUCAGACCUUCCAACUAAUAUUUUGUGAAGGCCAUUAUUGACCUCAAUGCUGCCAAAUCCAUGAGAAACUUCUUUUCCUUCCUCUCUCCUGAACUCUUGACACACAUGACCAGUUUUUAUGCCUCAAUUCUCCUAACUUUUUACUCCUUAACUCUCCCUAACUCUCAUGACAUCAUUACCUCCCAAUUUUCUUAUCUUUCUUGUGAGUCUUUCCCAGUCUUCGUUGUCCUGCCGUGCUAUCUCCCUAGAUACUCGGAGUUAUUCUUAUGGAUUUAAAUAUGAUCUCUAUCACAAGGCCUCUUAAAUUUUUAUCUCCAAACCACAAUUUUUCUCUGAGAUUUAGAUUUAUAUAUUCAACUUCCUACUUAUCAACACUGCCUGGAUUGGACUUGUCAAUAAUUUAAAACUUAACAUGUCAAAAUUGAUUUCUUAAAAUUUCUAACCAUGAAAGCUUGAUGCUUUUGUUUCCUUGUGUUUCUUCUAGAAAAUUUUAAAUAUUCUAUUUUGCUUCCUUUUCUUACAACCAUAAUUCCAAUCAAUUAUUAAUGUAUGCCAACAAUCUUUUCACAAAAUAUAUUCUUAAAUCAAUUUAUUUCUUAUACUCUUUAGUGUUUCUACCCUGGUGUAAAUUACCAACAUCUCUCAAUUGGAUUAAUGUAAUAAUAUUCUACCCAUGCUCCUUUCUCCUACUCUCAUUCUAUUCUAAUAUAUUUUCCACAUAAAAUAUAAAGUAAUGUAUUUGAAAUCUGAAUUGUAUAUACCAUUUUAUAAAAACAUGAGAAAUUCUCAAUUGCCCUUAAGAUAAAAUUCAAAGCCUCACCAUACUUUAUAAGGCUAUAAACGGAAUUCUUCCCUGCCUUCCUCUUCAACAUAGAUUCAUACCUCUACUCCCUCAGCUCCCUCUUUCCUAGCUACAUGAUUACUCUUUCAGGUCUUCAAAUACAUUAUGGAUUUUUCUGGCUUCAGGAUCUUCACUCCGUUUUUUCCCCAACAUUUCAUUUGGUUCACUCCUCCUAAUUGUGUGAUUUUCUGUUCAAAUAUCAAUUUCCAGUGAUGCUAGCUUUGAGAGGACUUCUGAACACUCAGUCUAAUUUAUGUCACUCAUUUUUAUCUCUGAAGUAUGUUUUGCUUCUCUUCAAAAUAUGUAUGGCAAUUUAUGUGUUUGUGGACAUUUAUGUAUAUAUACAUAGAUAUAGUUUGUCAUUCUUUCCUACAAGUAUCUAUAAACUAGAUUUGGUCUCAAAUUAUUUCAGAUUUUUUAUUUGUUGUGUGUCCAGAAACUAACACAGCACCUAAAUAGGAUGAGUAUUCAAUGCAAUCGUAAUGAAUGAAACAUGUGAUGAAUUUUACCCACACCUGGUCAAUAAUAUAUUUGGCCUUUAACAAUGACAUAAUGAUUCUAAUCAUUACUGAAACCCACUGUUCUAUAGAAUGCAUCGGUCUUCCCUAUUUGUACUCACCAGUUUUCUGCACAUCCCACCUCAACUUGUCUCACAUCUGCCUUUUGAAUUUCCUUGGAUAAUACUGGUAACUAGUCCUUGCUUAGCUACUGUGCAUCAUACUAGGUUAAUUUUCUGGAUCUGUAUUUUUUUUUUUCACUCACAAACUUUGGUGGGCAUGUAAGCUAUCCCUAGAUAAUAUUCAUUUUUAACAUGAUAUGGUUAUGCGUAAACAUAAAUUUUCAUGUCAUUUGGGAAAAUGCAUAAGUAUAGGAUUGCUAGGUCACACGAUAAAUGUAUGUUUAUAAUUAGCUGUCUAACUGUUUUCCAAAGACUAGUGCUUUUUGGGUCCCUCCGCUGUGGUACAAUGUGGGGCAUGUGUAGUGAGAGUUCAUUCAGCCUGGGCAGCUUUCCUGAGCUGUGGGAAUGGGCUUGUGAUGAACCCCAGGCUUCUGUUUCUCAUUGCUGCAUGUCUAUGAGUAACAAAUCUGCUUUUCUUGAUUUGUUGUGUGUUUUAUCUCAGCAGGUUCAUGAACUAGGUAGAGAACCUUUGCAUAUAUAUGUAUGUCCUUUUCUCCAAAUCCUCCCUGCUGUCAUCCGCACUAUUUUAUCAUAUAUUUUUGUAAAAUAAACACACAGUACAUUGC